CUCUGUGGAGUCUAGCUGCCAGGGUCGCGGCAGCUGCGGGGAGAGAUGACUGGGGAGCGACCCAGCACGGCGCUCCCGGACAGACGCUGGGGGCCGCGGAUUCUGGGCUUCUGGGGAGGCUGUAGGGUUUGGGUGUUUGCCGCGAUCUUCCUGCUGCUGUCUCUGGCAGCCUCCUGGUCCAAGGCUGAGAACGACUUCGGUCUGGUGCAGCCGCUGGUGACCAUGGAGCAACUGCUGUGGGUGAGCGGGAGACAGAUCGGCUCAGUGGACACCUUCCGCAUCCCGCUCAUCACAGCCACUCCGCGGGGCACUCUUCUCGCCUUUGCUGAGGCGAGGAAAAUGUCCUCAUCCGAUGAGGGGGCCAAGUUCAUCGCCCUGCGGAGGUCCAUGGACCAGGGCAGCACAUGGUCUCCUACAGCGUUCAUUGUCAAUGAUGGGGAUGUCCCCGAUGGGCUGAACCUUGGGGCAGUAGUGAGCGAUGUUGAGACAGGAGUAGUAUUUCUUUUCUACUCCCUUUGUGCUCACAAGGCCGGCUGCCAGGUGGCCUCUACCAUGUUGGUAUGGAGCAAGGAUGAUGGUGUUUCCUGGAGCACACCCCGGAAUCUCUCCCUGGAUAUUGGCACUGAAGUGUUUGCCCCUGGACCGGGCUCUGGUAUUCAGAAACAGCGGGAGCCACGGAAGGGCCGCCUCAUCGUGUGUGGCCAUGGGACGCUGGAGCGGGACGGAGUCUUCUGUCUCCUCAGCGAUGAUCAUGGUGCCUCCUGGCGCUACGGAAGUGGGGUCAGCGGCAUCCCCUACGGUCAGCCCAAGCAGGAAAAUGAUUUCAAUCCUGAUGAAUGCCAGCCCUAUGAGCUCCCAGAUGGCUCAGUCGUCAUCAAUGCCCGAAACCAGAACAACUACCACUGCCACUGCCGAAUUGUCCUCCGCAGCUAUGAUGCCUGUGAUACACUAAGGCCCCGUGAUGUGACCUUCGACCCUGAGCUCGUGGACCCUGUGGUAGCUGCAGGAGCUGUAGUCACCAGCUCCGGCAUUGUCUUCUUCUCCAACCCAGCACAUCCAGAGUUCCGAGUGAACCUGACCCUGCGAUGGAGCUUCAGCAAUGGUACCUCAUGGCGGAAAGAGACAGUCCAGCUAUGGCCAGGCCCCAGUGGCUAUUCAUCCCUGGCAACCCUGGAGGGCAGCAUGGAUGGAGAGGAGCAGGCCCCCCAGCUCUACGUCCUGUAUGAGAAAGGCCGGAACCACUACACAGAGAGCAUCUCCGUGGCCAAAAUCAGUGUCUAUGGGACACUCUGAGCUGUGCCACUGCCACAGGGGUAUUCUGCCUUCAGGACUCUGCCUUCAGGAACACAGGUCUGUAGAGGGUCUGCUGGAGACGCCUGAAAGACAGUUCCAUCUUCCUUUAGACUCCAGCCUUGGCAAAAUCACCUUCCCUUUACCAGGGAAAUCACUUCCUUUAGGACUGAAAGCUAGGCGUCCUCUCCCACAAAAAAGUCCUGCCCUCAUCUGAGAAUACUGUCUUUCCAUAUGGCUAAGUGUGGCCCCACCACCCUCUCUGCCCUCCCGGGACAUUGAUUGGUCCUGUCUUGGGCAGGUCUAGUGAGCUGUAGAAUUGAAUCAAUGUGAACUCAGGGAACUGGGGAAGGCUGAGCCUCCUCUUUGGUGUUGCGGUAAGAUAACCGACAGGGCUGGUGAAAGUCCCCAGAUGGCAGGAUAUUUGGUUUCAGAGUAAGGACUAGGUGCACCACCAUGACUGACUAUCAAUCAAAAUGUUUGUAACUUAAAAUUUUUAAUGAAGGAUAAUGAAUAUUUGUAGAGUCUCUAUGGUUCUGUCAAUGCACAUCUUCGUGUCUGUUUUCCUCAUGUAUCCUUGUGAGCCUGGGUGAGUUCUGGGGAGAGACCUGAUGUGCGUACUGCCUGUGAAAAUCUGACUUUGGCAAAUCAAAUCCUCUUUUCCUUUUGACAUGCCCUCUUUUUUUGUUGUUGCUUUUUUUGAGACAGGGCUCGCUCUGUCACCCAGGCUGGAGUGCAGUUGCACAAUCACGGCUCACUGAAGCCUCAACCUCCUGGGCUCAAGUGAUCCUCAUGUCUCAGCCUCCGGAGUAGUUGGGACUACAGGUCAGUGACACCAUGCCUGGUUAAUUUUUUUAAUUUUUAUUUUCAGUAGAGACAAGGUUGCGCUAUGUUGCCCAGGCUGGUAUGGAACUCCUGUGCUUAAGCAAUCCUCAUGCCUCAGCUUCCCAAAGUGCUGAGGUUACAGCUAUGAGCCACCGCACCCAGCCUACAUUCCUUCUUAUCACCGAGAAACAGGUUGAUCUUCACAGGUGUAAUGAGUAUGAAGGGAGUGCCAUAAGAUAUUUUUUAUUUUUUAUUUAUUUAUUUUUUAAUUUAAUUUUUUUUUUUUUUGAGAUGGAGUCUUGCUCUGGCACCCAGGCUAGAGUGCAGUGGUGCGAUCUCGGCUCACUGCAACCUCUGCCUCCCAGGUUCAAGCGAUUCUUCUGCCUCAGCUUCCCGAAUAGCUGGGAUUACAGGUGCCCACCACCACACCCGGCUAAUUUUUGUAUUUUUAGUAGAGACGGAGUUUCACCAUGUUGGCCAGGCUGGUCUCAAACUCCUGGCCUCAGGUGAUCCACCCGCCUCGGCCUCCCAAAGUGUUGUGAUUACAAGCAUGAGCCAUGGUGCCGGCGGGCUGAUUUUUUUAAUUUUUAGUAGAGACAAAGUCUCACUAUAUUGCCUAGGUUGGUCUCAAACUGCUGAGCUCAAGCAAUCUGCCGGCCAUGUUCUCUCAAAGUGCUGGGAUUACAGGCUUGAGCCCCUGCACCCAGCCUGUAAGAUAUUUUAAAAUCCACACUUGGCCAAGCGUGGUGGCUCACACAUAUAAUCCCAGCACUUUGGGAGGCCAAGGUGGGCGGAUCACAAGGUCAGGAGUUCGAGACCAGCCUGGCCAAUAUGGUGAAAUCCCAUCUCUACUAAAAAUACAAAAACUAGCCAGGCGUGUUGGCUUACACUUAUAGUCCCAGCUACUCAGGUGGCUGAGGCAGGAGAAUCACUUGAACCAGGAGGCGGAGUUUGCAGUGAGCUGAGAUCACAGCACUGCACACCAGCCUCGGCAACAGAGUGAGACUCCGUCUGAAAAAAAAAAAAUCCACGCUGUUUUAUAUUUCUAACAUGGGGUAGGAUACCAUCCUCCAUGAAAUAGGGUGCAAGUGUGUGAAAUGCAGAUGGGAAUCCUGUCCCAGCUAGCCUGACAGAGAAGUGAGCACUUCCUAUGGCAAAUUAUGUAAGAAAAUAUUCCCCAGGCAGAUGCUUAUGAAAAGAAUCUGUUCAGCCUGCAGGUAAGUGGGAGAGCCCUUGCUC